AUGGAUACUGAGGAAGGGUUGGUGUCCUUUGAAGAUGUGGCUCUGCACUUCACCUGGGAGGAGUGUCAGGGCCUGGAUGAUGCUCAGAGGACCCUCUACAGGGACGUGAUUGUGGAGACCUACAGCAGCCUGGUAUCAUUGGGGCAUUGCAUUACCAAACCUGAGAUGAUCUUCAAGCUAGAGCAAGGAGCAGAGACAUGGAUAGUAGAAGAAAUACCAAACCUGAGACUUUCAGGUGGAAGCAGGAAGCGAGUUUUCUCAGGUGUUUGCCACAGGAGCCUGGUGAAGCUCCAG